AUGGACAAGAUAAACCAGACAUUUGUGAGAGAAUUCAUUCUUCUGGGACUCUCUGGUUACCCCAAACUUGAGAUCAUUUUCUUUGCUCUGAUUCUAGUUAUGUACGUAGUGAUUCUAAUUGGCAAUGGUGUUCUGAUCAUAGCAAGCAUCUUGGAUUCUCGUCUUCACAUGCCCAUGUACUUCUUCCUGGGCAACCUCUCUUUCCUGGAUAUCUGCUAUACAACCUCCUCCAUUCCCUCAACACUGGUGAGCUUAAUCUCAAAGAAAAGAAACAUUUCCUUCUCUGGAUGUGCAGUGCAGAUGUUCUUUGGGUUUGCAAUGGGGUCAACAGAAUGUUUCCUCCUUGGCAUGAUGGCAUUUGAUCGUUAUGUGGCCAUCUGUAACCCUCUGAGAUACCCCAUCAUCAUGAACAAGGUGGUGUAUGUACUGCUGACUUCUGUAUCAUGGCUUUCUGGUGGAAUCAAUUCAACUGUGCAAACAUCACUUGCCAUGCGAUGGCCUUUCUGUGGGAACAAUAUUAUUAAUCAUUUCUUAUGCGAGAUCUUAGCUGUCCUAAAAUUAGCUUGUUCUGAUAUAUCUGUCAAUAUUGUUACCCUAGCAGUGUCAAAUAUUGCUUUCCUAGUUCUUCCUCUGCUCGUGAUUUUUUUCUCCUAUAUGUUCAUCCUCUACACCAUCUUGCGAACGAACUCGGCCACAGGAAGACACAAGGCAUUUUCUACAUGCUCAGCUCACCUGACUGUGGUGAUCAUAUUUUAUGGUACCAUCUUCUUUAUGUAUGCAAAACCUAAGUCCCAGGACCUCCUUGGGAAAGACAACUUGCAAGCUACAGAGGGGCUUGUUUCCAUGUUUUAUGGGGUUGUGACCCCCAUGUUAAACCCCAUAAUCUAUAGCUUGAGAAAUAAAGAUGUAAAAGCUGCUAUAAAAUAUUUGCUGAGCAGGAAAGCUAUUAACCAGUAA